GUCAGUUGUUAUCUGUUCGGGGCGCCGCCGCCGCCUCACGAGCCCGGUGCCCAGGAGCCCGGCCGCCUCCCGCCUGCCGCCUGCCGCGCCCGCCCGGCCCCGCCCGCUCGGCCCGAUCGCCGCGCCGCGCGCAUGGGGCGCGCCCCCGGGGGGGCGGCCGAGGGCCGCUGAGCGCCGGGCCCGCCCCCGCCGAUGCGCCCAGCCGCCCGCGCCGGGGGUCCCAGGCCGCGCCGGGCCCGGGGCUGAGCCGCCCCCCGCGCCCGGCAUGCCCGGCCCGGCCCGCCGCCCGCCGCCGCCCAGGGCCCGAGCCCGCGCGGCGCACACUCAGCCCGGCGGCGCCGCGUAGCCGAGGGAGCCCGCCUGCUGCGAGCCAGGCGCGGGGCGUCAAGGUCACCGGCCCGACGGGGCGCACGCGCGGCCAUGGAGGCCAAGGUCCGCCCGAGCCGGCGCUCGCGCGCGCAGCGGGACCGUGGCCGGCGCCGGGAGGCCGCCCGCGACGCCCGCGCCCAGAGUCCGUCGUCGGGCGACGAGCCCGAGCCCAGCCCCGGCAAGGAGAACGCGGGCCUCCGCGGCGCGCCCCCCCGAGGCGCCGCCCCCGCGCCCCGCACCGCGCGUCCCCCGCGCCGCCGCCGCCGCGAGUCCAGCUCGCAGGAGGAGGAGGUCAUCGACGGCUUCGCCAUCGCCAGCUUCAGCACCCUGGAGGCCCUGGAGCUGUGCCCUCCCCGAGAGGAUUCUGUCCUUUCGUGGACGCUUCUCCCUGGCCGGCUGGCUCCUCUGGACCCUAAACUUGACGCGCCGUAUCUGUCUGCACCAGCCCUGGUGCCAGGAGCUGAGCCAGCAUACAGAAGAAGGAUAUGGCCCUGAAGCCACAUGAGCGGAAGGAGAAGUGGGAGCGUCGUCUCAUCAAGAAGCCCCGGGAGUCGGAAACCUGCCCCCCUGCGGAGCCCAGUGAGAACAGGCGGCCCCUGGAGGCAGGCAGCCCCGGGCAGGACCUCGAACCCGCCUGCGAUGGGGCGAGAAAGGUCCCACUGCAGCCCUCCAAGCAGAUGAAGGUCACCGUGUCCAAAGGGGGCGACCGGGACAGUGACGACGACAGCGUCCUCGAAGCCACCAGCUCCCGGGACCCGCUCAGCGAUAGCUCUGCGCAUGCGGUCUCGGGGAGAGGCUACUCUUGUGACAGCGAGAGCGGCCCGGACGACAAGGCAUCCGUGGGCUCUGAGAAGCUCUUUGCGCCGGGAACCGAUAAAGGCCCAGCGCUUGAGAAGUCGGAGGCCAAGGCCGGGCCGGUGCCCAAGGUGUCAGGCCUGGAGCGCAGCCGCGAGCUCAGCGCCGAGAGCUUCCUGCCCACUGCCAGCCCCGCGCCCCAUGCCGCGCCCUGCCCGGGGCCCCCGCCCGGCUCCCGCGCCAAUCCCUUGGUGAAGAAGGAACCCCCCGCCCCGCACCGCCACACCCCGCAGCCGCCACCCCCGCAGCCCCGCGGCCUGCUCCCGACACACGUGCCUGCAUCCCUGGGCGCCUUCGCGGGCCACAGCCAGGCGGCAGCCAACGGCCUGCACGGCCUCAGCAGGAGCAGCAGCGCCCCCCUGGGCCUGGGGAAGCACGUGUCGCUGUCGCCACACGGGCCGGGCCCCCACCUGUCUACCUCACACCUGGCGCUCCGGUCCCAGGCGCAGCACCAGCUCCACGCGGCCAUGUUUGCCGCACCCCCGACACUGCCCCCGCCCCCGGCGCUGCCGGCCAGCAGCCUGGUCCUCCCAGGACACCCGGCCGAUGCCAGCCUGGCGGUCUCAUUCAGCCAGCCAAUCAUGUAUUGCCAGCCUCAUUCGGGAAUUCUGAUUGAUCACGAGCUGCUCAGGCAAGAGCUGAACACGCGGUUUCUGGUGCAGAGCGCCGAGCGGCCUGGCGCCUCCCUGGGCCCGGGGGCUCUGCUGCGGGCGGAGUUCCAUCAGCACCAGCACACACACCAGCACACGCACCAACACACACACCAGCACCAACACACAUUCGCCCCCUUCCCCGCAGGGCUGCCCCCGACGCCGCCCGCCGCACCCCCGCCGUUUGACAAGUAUGCGCCCAAGCUGGACAGCCCCUACUUCCGACAUUCCAGCGUGAGUGCAGAGGGUGGGGUGAGGACUUGGGCCCCCCCUCCAUCCGCUCUCCUUCUCUUACAGUUCUUCCCGUCCUUCCCUCCUGCCAUCCCGGGACUGCCCACCCUGCUCCCACACCCCGGCCCCUUCGGGUCCCUGCAGGGCGCUUUUCAGCCUAAGACUUCAAGCCCCAUUGAGGUGGCCCGCCGGGCUGGUGCGGUUCACACACUCCUGCAGAAAGCGCCUGGGGUGUCUGACCCGUACCGGGCGGUGGUCAAGAAGCCGGGGAGGUGGUGUGCCGUGCACGUGCAGAUCGCCUGGCAGAUCUACCGUCACCAGCAGAAGAUAAAGGAGAUGCAGCUGGACCCCCACAAGCUGGAGGUGGGUGCAAAGCUGGACCUGUUCGGCAGACCCCCUGCCCCGGGCGUGUUUGCAGGCUUCCACUACCCACAGGACCUGGCCCGGCCCCUCUUCCCCAGCACAGGGCAUGCGAGAGAAUGGGAGGUGAAGGUUCACAGAGGAAAUUGGGGUGCUCCCUGUGAACAGAGCUGCAGAUGGGAGGCCCUGGUGCUCUCUCCUGGCUUCUGUCAAACCUGGCUGCCCCCCCCAGGUGCCGCCCAUCCUGCCUCCAACCCAUUUGGACCCUCAGCCCAUCCUGGCAGCUUCCUGCCCACUGGCCCCCUGACAGACCCUUUCAGCAGACCGAGCACCUUUGGGGGCCUGGGCAGCCUGAGCAGCCACGCCUUUGGGGGCCUGGGCAGCCAUGCACUGGCUCCCGGUGGCAGCAUCUUUGCCCCCAAGGAGGGCUCCUCCGUGCACGGCCUGCCCAGCCCCCAUGAGGCCUGGAACCGACUGCACCGGGCACCGCCCUCCUUCCCGGCUCCGCCCCCGUGGCCCAAGUCCGUGGACGCGGAGCGGGUGUCAGCCCUGACCAACCAUGACCGAGAGCCGGACAAUGGCAAGGAGGAGCAGGAACGGGACCUCCUGGAGAAGACGCGCCUGCUGAGCCGGGCCUCGCCCGCCACCCCCGCUGGCCACCCCGUCAGCGGCCUCCUGCUCCGGGCCCAGAGCGAGCUGGGCCGGUCCGGGGCCCCCGCGGAGCGCGAGGCCGAACCUCGGGUCAAGGAGAGCCGCUCCCCGGCCAAGGAGGAGGCCGCCAAGAUGCCCGCGCGCGCAUCCCCGCCCCACAGCAAGGCGGCCCCUGGAGACGUGAAGGUCAAGGAGGAGCGCGGGGAGGACGAGGCCUCCGAGCCCCCGGCGGGCGGCCUGCACCCCGCGCCCCUGCAGCUCGGCCUGGGCCGCGAGCGCCUGGGCGCGCCGGGCUUCGCGUGGGAGCCUUUCCGCGGCCUGGAGCUGCCACGUCGCGCCUUCCCCGCUGCCGCCCCCGCCCCGGGCUCCGCCGCCCUCUUGGAGCCCCCGGAGCGCCCCUACCGCGACCGCGAGCCCCACGGCUACAGCCCCGAGCGCCUGCGCGGGGAGCUGGAGCGCGCGCGGGCCCCGCACCUGCCGCCCGCCGCCCCCGCCUUGGACGGCGCGCUGCUGCCCUCGCUGGGAGCCCUGCACUUCCCGCGCCUCUCGCCCGCCGCGCUGCACAAUGGGCUCCUGGCGCGGACCCCGCCCGCCGCCGCCGCCCUCGGCGCACCGCCCCCCCUGGUGACGGCGGCCGGGCCCCCCACGCCCCCCGGGCCGCCGCGGAGCCGGACUACUCCGCUGGGGGGCCUCGGGCCGGGCGAGGCGCGCGACUACUCCCCGUCCCGAAAUCCCCCGGAGGUGGAGGCGCGGUAGCCCCGGGGCCGCAGACGCCUCUCCGAGCGGAGCGCACCGCUGUCCGUCUCUCCAUCAGUUCCUAGAACUCAAGCACAGCUCCCGCCGAUCCUGGGGCGGCGCCGCCUCUCCACCCGCAGCCUGCGGAGGCGGGGACUUGGGUGUCGGCUUUUCUGAGGGUGAUCUUUUGUUUUCCGAGUUUGGGAUUCGGCUGUUGGGAAAAAAAAAUCGCGUUUGUACCUUUUCCCCCCACAGAUGAGAAGUGUUUGUAAUGGAUUUGUAUUUUUCUUAAUUUUAUGCUCUUUAGACGUUUAAAAGAACCAAAAAAGAAACUUUUGCUUCUUCGUUUUCGGUUGGGAUUUGCAGUUUAAUGGCCUCAGAUCCUUCUCCAGAUCCCCAGGGUUUCUUUGUCUUAUUUAUGGAGAAAAACCGGUCACUUUGUCCAGCGCACUGUGAGGCCCCCACUCAGGCCAGCCCUGGCCCCCCCUUGGUACUUGGAACCGAAGUUACAGAUUAUAUUAAAAUAAUAAUGUACAAAACUUUGUUUUUUUGCCUUAUUAUGCAGAAGUGUAAUUUCUUUUUUGGUUUGUUUUUUUAAAAGCAAACGAAACGUGUAAAUAGUCUGUUGAUAUAAAUAUAUGACGUUACUAAAUUCUUAAUCUAGAUAGACUUUAUAAAAACCGUUUCCAGAAACCCCUCUGGUUGUUUGUCUAACAUGGUCACAAAAACCCAGGCGCUGCUGGCUGUAAACAUUAUCAGAAGUUUAAUGGCAGCAACUUUCCUUCAACUAUGCAAGCGCUUCCCGGCGGCUCUGCUGGUUGGGGGAGGAAGGUUCCGCCAGCGACCUCCCAGCCCCUGGGUCCGUGGAGGGGUUGGGUCCCCCAGCAGAGCCCCUGGGCCAGCAGAACAGCACUCCUGGGCGGCUCCUGUGGGCUUCAGGACUGGCCGGCUCCAGCCGCAAGGGCGAUGCUGUGGACGUUUGUGUGGAUGGUGCAGUGUUCUUGGAAUCUGUAGACCAGAUCGGUGGAGGUAUAGAAGUGCAAGAGUCUAAAGGCUGAUUUUACACACACACACACACACACACACACACACACAAAAUCACUGCUGUGUGUUUUCUUCCGCCUGAGGCAUCAGCGUCACCUCGGUGUGGUCGUCGCCUCCCAGGCCCUUGGCCUGGCCUCCUCUCAGUUUGGGUUUUGCCCUCACCCACAUGAGCCCCCCCAUGCCCUGCCCCCCUUGCGGCCUUUUGUGUUCCCCGAUGUCUGGGCUGUGUCCCUGCCGGGAUUCCCAGCCUUCGGGGUCAGCCGUCGAGCCACUUGCUUUGCUCAGUUCUGUGUUUCAGCCACAUUUCCACGGUGGACCCUGUUUGUUUUAAAUAUUCUGUUCCCAUGUCAAUCAGUGACGAUAAAUACAGCCUUGAUUUGGAUGAAA